AGUGGCCUCUGCCAGUCUGGCAGACACUUGCAGACCUCUCUUCUCAGCACCACCAAUCUCUGAUGCCCUGCGAUGCCCACACUCAAUACUUCUGCCUCUCCACCCACAUUCUUCUGGGCCAAUGCCUCCGGAGGCAGUGUGCUGAGUGCUGAUGAUGCUCCGAUGCCUGUCAAAUUCCUAGCCCUGAGGCUCAUGGUUGCCCUGGCCUAUGGGCUUGUGGGGGCCAUUGGCUUGCUGGGAAAUUUGGCGGUGCUGUGGGUACUGAGUAACUGUGCCCGGAGAGCCCCUGGCCCACCUUCAGACACCUUCGUCUUCAACCUGGCUCUGGCGGACCUGGGACUGGCACUCACUCUCCCCUUUUGGGCAGCCGAGUCGGCACUGGACUUUCACUGGCCCUUCGGAGGUGCCCUCUGCAAGAUGGUUCUGACGGCCACUGUCCUCAACGUCUAUGCCAGCAUCUUCCUCAUCACAGCGCUGAGCGUUGCUCGCUACUGGGUGGUGGCCAUGGCUGCGGGGCCAGGCACCCACCUCUCACUCUUCUGGGCCCGAAUAGCCACCCUGGCAGUGUGGGCGGCGGCUGCCCUGGUGACGGUGCCCACAGCUGUCUUCGGGGUGGAGGGUGAGGUGUGUGGUGUGCGCCUUUGCCUGCUGCGUUUCCCCAGCAGGUACUGGCUGGGGGCCUACCAGCUGCAGAGGGUGGUGCUGGCUUUCAUGGUGCCCUUGGGCGUCAUCACCACCAGCUACCUGCUGCUGCUGGCCUUCCUGCAGCGGCGGCAACGGCGGCGGCAGGACAGCAGGGUCGUGGCCCGCUCUGUCCGCAUCCUGGUGGCUUCCUUCUUCCUCUGCUGGUUUCCCAACCAUGUGGUCACUCUCUGGGGUGUCCUGGUGAAGUUUGACCUGGUGCCCUGGAACAGUACUUUCUAUACUAUCCAGACGUAUGUCUUCCCUGUCACUACUUGCUUGGCACACAGCAAUAGCUGCCUCAACCCUGUGCUGUACUGUCUCCUGAGGCGGGAGCCCCGGCAGGCUCUGGCAGGCACCUUCAGGGAUCUGCGGUUGAGGCUGUGGCCCCAGGGCGGAGGCUGGGUGCAACAGGUGGCCCUAAAGCAGGUAGGCAGGCGGUGGGUCGCAAGCAACCCCCGGGAGAGCCGCCCUUCUACCCUGCUCACCAACCUGGACAGAGGGACACCCGGGUGAAGGGCGCAAGCUGAACACACUCCUCUUUCUGAGAUCCACCAAGUGUAGGAUCCUUGAGUCCUGGGGAGAAGCUGCCCUCUCUGCCAGGCUGCAGUGCCCUCAGGGAAAAGUCUGAUCUUUGAUCCCCAACUCUGGGUGUGGUGAAUGGGGGAGGCGGGGGCUCAGAUCAGAGCUGGAUGUGACAAAGCUUAAGUCUUUAUUUGGAGAUGGGAAAGAAGAGGAUCUGAGAAUAAACCUCUGGAUUAUCCACAAA